GACAUGUGUGAUAUAGUAACUUUCUGUCUCUGAGAAGCAGUUUGGACCCAGCUGAAAAAUUUUAUUUAUGGAGACUUGUAAUCAGCCUGAUAUACAGAGAACACUCUGGACUGGAAAUAUAGUCAGGUACCAAGGUCUGCUAAUUUGGCCAUUGCCAGUGAUUCAAAACCACCUCCCCACCCUGAGUAAAAGAUUUGAUAUGAAUAUGAAUGCUAUGAGUCUCCUGGUGAUGUUUUGGGUGUAUAUGUUCCUGUGUGUGUUUGGAAAUCAUAGAGGGUAUUUACCUUGAGGGCUCUUUUGUUGACCUUAUUUAUUUGAAAUUCUUAUUUUAUUUGUAAUGGCAUAUGUAUAUUUUUGUGAUGCUACAUGCAAUCUCUGUGUAUACUUUUUGUAUAUAUGUAUACAUAUUUGUAAAUAUAUUGGUAUGCAGUGAUACAGUAUGUGUAUAUUAUGUACCCAUACCCAUUGUGGGCUGAAUUUAUUUAAGUUCUGUGAGGACAUCCUAGUGGCAUUGUUCAUGCUGCUGUAAUUAGGUUGUGGCUGUAUCUCAUUCAUAAGCCUCUAUUUUGAGAGGCUUGUGUUUGGAUAAAAUGGGCUAAUUUGGAGUUGAAAUUAGGAUAUGAAGAUCUUAACAGAAAGCUAGAUAUUUAUUCUUAGCUUUAAAAUCACCUGCAAAUUUUUAUUUAAACUGAUGAUAAAUUAGUGAUAUAACCUGAAAAACCUAAGUAUGUGAAACUGAGACACCAGCAGAUUCUUAGGCUGUAGUAGUCCUUUAUUUUCUUGAUCCAUAUUUAAGUAUUAUUACUGAGUAGUAAAUUAUGUAUAUUGGGGCUUAAUAGAGAGGCUGUGGAAAAAAAUUGCUUUAAUCACAUUUAAAAACAUAGGAAAAUGUCCAUUAAAUAGGGGAAAUAUAUUCCCAGUUGUCAUUUUUAUGCCUCAUACUGAAUUUUGAUUUUGGAACAAUUCUUUUUUCAUCAGUGUUUUAUGUGUCUCUAUGAGGCAGAAAAGGGGGCAUUAGCUAAGGGAUGGCCUAACCUAAGUAGGAUAGGAUUUAGUGAGGAACGGGAGGUUGUUAAUUUGUAUAUUUGCAGCAGCUAUGAUUAAUUUAGUCCUGUCUUGGCAUUUCCGGCUACAGAUUUUUUCUUACUGGACUUGCAUAUCAAAGGUGAGUAGGCUCAUCUGAGAAAAUGCUUCCACUGAAUAAAAUGCCUUCACUCGUAUUGCUGUGUCUCUAUGAGACCACUUGUGUUCUGCAAGUUGAUGAUAUAUUCGCACAUGAAGUAGAGUUUUUAAUAUUAGAUGCAUGGUGUGCUAUAAAAAUCUGGGCCUUCAAACCUCUCCCAAGGAUGAUAGGGUUGGGGAGGAUAAGAGGAUAGUAAAUACGUGCAAUGCCAAUUUGUGAACCUAUAGAAUGUUGCCAAGUAUCAAUGUUUGGUUACUUCAGUUGACAUAUUUAUUUGCAUGAAAGAGUGUAGGAGAUGUUUAAUAUACACUUAAAUACAUUCACUGCAGAAAUUAAGUAGAGGUUAUUUUUGCAUGAUAAAAUAUAACUGCAAAGCAACUUUUUACACCGUAUUCUUUGGAAGAUUAAAUCUAUCUGAUCCAAUAUUAUCUUAAAAUAGAGAAAUUAUCUCAGGAGUCUGUUUUACCACCCAAAAAAAUGUUACAUUUGCUGAUUCAUUAUAUUUUAAAUAAAACAGCCAACUAUUCAUAAGACUUUUCAAUUAUAGUAUUAAAUUCAGAAAUAAUUAUAACAGCAUUUUUCUUGAAUAAAUAUUAAAAUUUGGUAAUUUAUUAUUUCUGAAAAAUCAGUGAAAACAUCCAUAGGAUCUGAUGGUUUGUUGUUUGAAUAACCAAAUCAUUGUUUUUGCACUGGAGAGUAGUAGAGCAGAUAUUAUACCAUUUAAAAUUCAUGGAACUGACUCAGGCUCCUUGUGGAUAUUAAUUUGAGGACAGUAGUGGUAAUCAAAAGUACAGUAGAAAACACUUGACAUUGUGAAUGUGACCUCUGACCCCAACCGUUGUAAAGCCAAUAACUUUGAGGGUGAAUAAGGUAACACUUGCUUAGAAAACCCAGCCCUUUCCCCCAGUCUCCUGCGCUCUUAUACAUUGAUACUUUACAACUAUUUUUGCUGUACCUCUCAGUCUUUCCUGGAUAAUGGGACCACUUAAAAAAAAAAGUGAUUCAUCUUCCUCAAACUAGAAUUUCAAAGCCUAAUACUACACUAUGUUCCAGCUUCACUGAGUUUUGAACAAAAAGACUUAAGCAUGCCUUGUGUUUAAGGAAAAAUAAUUGAUGUGUGAAUGGAAUCAAUCACCUAUUGACGGGAAGGGUGUCAGGAUGAUGUAGGGUGAUAUGCCUUUAAUUGGAUAAAGAGAACUGUAUUAAGUAUAACUAAUUUAAUAACUGAUUGAAGCACCAUUCUUAAUUUUAAAAUAUUUUUGUUAAUUUCUUUUGUGGUUUUAAAAAUUAAUAAUUUUUUUUUUUUUGAGAUGGAGUUUUGCUCGUUGCCCAGGCUGGAAUGCAAUGGCGCGAUCUCAGCUCACUGCAACCUCCGCCUCCUGGGUUCAAGAGAUUCUCCUGCCUCAGCCUCCCAAGUAGCUGGGAUUACAGGCGUGUGCCACCACGACCAGCUAAUUUUGUAUUUUUAGUAGAGAUGGGGUUUCACCAUGUUGGCCAGGUUGGUCUCGAACUCCUGACCUCAAGUGAUCCACCCGCCUCGGCCUCCCAAAGUGCUGGGAUUACAGGUGUGAGCCACUGUGGCCGGCCUAAAAAAAAUUCUUUUUAAUAGUUAUCAGACUACUUUAACCAGUGCCAUGUUUAAACAUACUUGGACAAUAGACUCAGUUUUUUUAAUAGUUUGAAGUACAUUAUAUUAAAACUACAAACUCACUUAUUCAAGCCUAAAUUUCAUCAUAGACUAUAAAUUGGGUAUCAAUUUCCUAUUUUGGUGGACAAUUCCAGUCUGUCUACUACGACAAUCAUCUUUUUAGGUGUAAUAUUGUUUAAGACAUAGGUAAUUUUAGGUUUUAUACUUUUCUCCUAGGCUUAUGGAAUGAAAGCUAAUAGGAUAUCACUUUCAGAAUGAAAUAGGGAAUUAUGGCUAGCCUUCUUAUAGGGCUGCCGUAAAUGAUACUUAAAUGUUUGUUAUAUCACUGAUUUUCUUUUCUCUUCUGAAGCUGUUGUGAAUGUCCACUUUGCCAUGAUUAAAAGUUGAGAUUUGUAAACAUUACAAUUUGAACCAUAAAUUUUCUCAAACAUGAAAUCAGUAUGAAUAAGUAUAAAAUUUGAAAUGAUCAUACAUGAGAAUCCCAAAAGUAAAUACUUCCAAACCAUAGAGGGAUAACCACUGUAUUUUUAAAAAGCUUAUUUCCACCCUUAAAGAAGCAUGCUACUAAUUGCUUUUUUUCUAAAUUAAAACUAUGUACUGUGGUAAAUUAAAAAUCUGCAGGAAAAAUUGCUUAGUGUUUUAGCACAAUAAGAAUUUUUAUUACUCAGGAGUUGGAGACCAGUCUGGGCAAUACAGUGAAACCCUGUCGCUACUAAAAUACAAAAAAAAAAAAAAAAAAAAAAAAAUUAGCCAGGCAUGGUGGUGUGCGCCUGUAAUCCCAGCUACUUGGGAGGCUGAGGCAGGAGAACUGCUUGUAACCUGGGAGGCGGAGGUUGCAGUGAGCCGAGAUCGUGCCAUUGCACUCCAGUCUGGGUGACAGAGCAAGACUCAUUCUCAAAAAAAAAAAAAAAAGGAAUUUUUAUUACUAUUUCCUGAAGAAUGGUUUUUGUUAACUUGUUACUGUAUCAUUAAAAAGACCUUCUAAUGGUUCAGUACAAUAAUCUAGAACUUGAUUUAUGUGGCUUUUUAUAGUUAUCUGAAUGCAUUCCUUUUGCCACAUAGACCAUAUGGCUAGUUCUCCAACUUUUUUGCUUAUUUUUAAUAAACCUUGCUGUUCAACAAUCAGAGAAACCUUUAGAUUUUGGAUGAUUCUUCCAGUUGAGGUAGAAACAUCUUAGAUAAUAGGAAAGGCAAAUACAAAGUCCUAACAUUUUCAUAGUAGAGUUUACAAGUAAAAUAACUUAUCCAUAUAGGUUAUCUUCGUUGUGUAGCACCAGUAUAAAUAGUGAUUUCAUUAAUCAUUGAAUCAGAUGAAGCAGUUAUAAAUCACUUUUUACUUUGUGCUAAGAAUUAUUGUAAUUUCAGGACACUUUAUUAUUUCCUCUGAGCAGUUUCCAUUGGAAGGUUGAGUUUCCCUUUUUUAAGUUCUAAUCAUCACUAAAGGUUAAGAUAAUCAAAUAGGAGUUAAAAUAAGUUAUGUUUGAUCUUUUUCCCUUGAAAAUAAUGCUGAACUUAUUGUCUACAUUCUGAUUAUUAGGCAGAAAUGCACUUGUUUAAAUCAUAGAAGUAAUUCAUUUGGAGGAUAUAAUUACUCGAUUUUCUAGUGGUGUGAAAUACUUUUUAACAAUUGUGCUUGUCUGUAACUGAAAUGUUAUAGAAUUUUAACACUAUAGGGAUUAUAGAGUUAUAUUAGCUCUCCUCAAGAGACUGAAGCACAAUAUUUUUCAUGUAACAAUUCUUAUCCAAGUGCUGCUAAUCUGUCGUGCAAAUAAUGAAGCUAUUUGGUUGCCUAUUUAGCUAUUCACAAAUCACUGUAAUCUUUGAAACAAUCUUGUCGUUCAUUUGUAUUAAUAUUUGGAUAUUGUGAGUUAAUACUUUAGAAAAAAAUCCAUCAACUCAGCCCCGUUAGCAAAACUGUUUGGAUUCAUAGUUUUUAUAUGUGUUAACAGUAGAAUAAAUUUUGAAGGGGCUAUUUACUACCAAUGACUAAGGGGAAAAUUAUACUGUCACUAUCAUUUGACUUGAACAUUUGUGGUAUUGUAAAAGUCUUGUCAGUUGUGUUCUAAAUUGCUUAAGCCAUACGUUCUCUUAAACAGGAUGUUUUUUUCUUCCUUUCCAGCAGCCUUUUUCUUCUUUGUCUGUUAUGGUUAAUACUCCAUAGAUUUUAGAAAUUGAGAAGUUCUUGAAACAUUUUAUUUUCUUGAGUUCAUCACUUUUGACUCUUGUAUGAGAUGUGAUUUGUCAUAAAAGAUAGCCUUCCACUACUUCACUAAAUGAAUUUCAGAGUAAACACUGUGAUUCUGCAGAGCGGAUUCAGUAGGCUUUCCAAUGUUUUCUCCUGCUAUACAGUGCCUACCACCUUGAGGGCACUUCAGUACUAGAGGAUGAAAACUGAAACGUUGUUUUGAUGUUUAUUGAAUAACGAGAUUAGAGAAUAUUUGAUUUUUGUUGUCAGUGUAUUAAAGAAAUUUUCACAUUGAUAAAUGUUCUCUAGGAAUGUGUCUACAUUCAUCAGGUGUGAACUCUUGUACAUGAAUUUUGUACCUUGAAUCCACAUAUAUAUUAAGUGUAUCAUCAAUAUAAAAAUAAACAUUAUUUGCUUAAAGUUUUUGGUACUUUUUCGGUAUUGACAGCUGAACUGUUAGGGUUUGCUUCAUUCAAAUAUCUCAGAGGCUUUGAACUAUCUUGGGGUUGAUGCUUCUUGUUAGUUUGUCAAUGUUUGAAUCCUGGUUUUGGUUUUUUCCCUGCCCUGCUCCUGCAGGUCAGAACUGGAACACGCGAGGGAAGGGACUGUUGAAGAAUUGGGUGGAAUCUGCUUAUUCUUGGGCUUGUGUUGAGUCUGGGGAUGGAACCAGAGUUCCUUAAGGUGGAAUGGCUGGCUUGGCAUUGACGAGUUCAGGGACCUGACUUAGGGUACUGAUUUGGACCGUGACUUUUUGUUUGAGAUAGAGUUUCGCUCUUGUUGCCCAGGCUGGAGUGCAAUGGCGCGAUCUUGACUCACUGCAACCUACACCUCCCGGGUUCAAGCGAUUAUCCUGCCUCAGCCUCCCAAGUAAUUGGGAUUACAGGCAUGGGCCACCAUGCCCGGCUAAUUUUGUAUUUUUAGUAGAGACGAGGUUUCGCUAUGUUAGGCUGGUCUGAACUCCUGACCUCGGGUGAACCACCCGCCUCGGCUUCUCAAAGUGUGGGGAUUACAGGAGUGAGCCACCGCGCCCGGCCUGGACUGUGACUUGGAACAAGAUAGUUUUUCCUCUUUUGUUUAUUUUCCUACUGCCUGCAUGAUUGCUAUUUAUUUAAAGAGACGGAGUCUCGCCACGGUGCCCAGGCUGGUCUGGAAGCCCUGGUCUCAAGAGAUCCUCCCACCUCGGUCUUCCGAGUAGCUGGGACCACAGAAGCGCGCGCCGUGCACUUUUGAUGUUUUCAACUUCCUUCCUAAGCAGAAAGGAGACGGCCCAGCAGCGGAUGGUGAAGCUAAUCCAAUAUAGUGAGCUGCCACCAGCGUUUUUAAGUGCAUUACAUAGACAGAAUGCUUUGACCUCCAAGCUGUUUUAAAUCUAGUAGAUAAGCCAGAUCCUGUGUUGCCAUAAGCCCUUGGCCCACAUUUAAGUGGGAAUGCAGCUAGCUUGGAUGUCUGAAACUUUGUAGGCGCCUCUGUCUGAAUCCUGAACACAGGCACCAGGACUACUGAGAGCUCGUCAUCUGUGCAGGAUAGCCACACAGCAAACAUGUUUGCAAAACUGAAGAAGAAAAUUGCAGAAGAGACUGCUGUUGCUCAGAGGCCAGGAGGUGCUACUAGGAUCCCACGGUCUGUGAGCAAGGAAUCAGUUGCCUCAAUGGGAGCUGACUCAGGAGAUGACUUUGCUUCCGAUGGAAGCAGCUCCAGAGAAGAUCUUUCAUCCCAGCUUCUGAGAAGGAAUGAACAGAUACGGAAGUUAGAGGCCAGACUUUCUGACUAUGCUGAACAGGUCCGAAACUUGCAGAAGAUAAAAGAGAAGCUUGAAAUUGCAUUAGAAAAACACCAGGAUUCUUCCAUGCGGAAAUUUCAAGAGCAGAAUGAGACAUUCCAAGCCAACAGAGCCAAAAUGGCAGAAGGACUGGCUUUGGCAUUAGCCAGAAAGGACCAGGAAUGGUCAGAAAAGAUGGAUCAGCUUGAAAAGGAGAAAAAUAUUCUGACAGCCCAGUUACAGGAAAUGAAGAACCAGAGUAUGAAUCUUUUCCAAAGGAGAGAUGAAAUGGAUGAAUUAGAGGGGUUCCAGCAGCAGGAACUAAGUAAAAUAAAGCACAUGCUUUUAAAAAAAGAAGAAAGUCUAGGGAAAAUGGAACAAGAAUUGGAGGCACGAACCAGAGAACUUAGUCGUACCCAGGAGGAGUUGAUGAACUCCAAUCAGAUGUCAUCAGACUUAAGCCAGAAGCUAGAAGAAUUGCAGAGACACUACUCAACGCUGGAAGAGCAGAGAGAUCAUGUGAUAGCUUCAAAAACAGGUGCAGAAAGUAAGAUCACAGCCCUGGAACAAAAGGAACAAGAGCUCCAAGCACUCAUUCAGCAGCUUUCCAUUGAUUUGCAAAAGGUCACUGCUGAAACUCAAGAGAAAGAAGACGUUAUCACACAUUUGCAAGAGAAGGUUGCAUCCUUGGAGAAGAGACUAGAACAGAACUUAUCAGGAGAAGAACACUUGCAAGAACUCCUGAAAGAGAAAACACUUGCUGAGCAGAAUUUGGAGGAUACCAGACAACAGCUCUUGGCAGCCAGAAGCAGCCAGGCUAAGGCCAUUAACACCCUGGAGACUCGGGUGAGAGAACUGGAGCAGACCUUGCAGGCCUCUGAGGAGCAGCUCCAACAGAGCAAGGGCAUUGUGGCUGCCCAGGAAACUCAGAUACAGGAGCUCGCUGCCGCCAACCAGGAGAGCAGCCAUGUGCAGCAGCAGGCCCUUGCUCUGGAGCAGCAGUUCUUGGAGCGCACCCAGGCGCUAGAAGCCCAGAUAGUGGCCCUGGAGAGAACGCGGGCAGCUGACCAGACCACCGCAGAGCAAGGGAUGAGACAACUGGAGCAAGAAAAUGCAGCCCUUAAAGAAUGCAGGAAUGAAUAUGAACGUUCUUUACAAAAUCACCAAUUUGAACUAAAGAAGCUGAAGGAAGAAUGGAGCCAAAGAGAAAUUGUGAGCGUGGCCAUGGCUCAAGCCCUGGAGGAGGUGCGGAAGCAAAGGGAAGAGUUCCAGCAACAGGCAGCUAACCUGACAGCCAUAAUAGACGAGAAGGAACAGAAUCUGCGGGAAAAAACCGAAGUGCUUCUCCAGAAAGAGCAGGAGAUUCUCCAGCUGGAGCGAGGUCACAACUCUGCCCUGCUGCAGAUACACCAGCUGCAGGCCGAGCUGGAGGCCCUGAGGACCCUCAAGGCGGAGGAGGCUGCAGUGGUCGCGGAGCAGGAGGACCUGCUGAGGCUGCGGGGCCCAUUGCAGGCCGAAGCACUCUCAGUCAAUGAGUCGCACGUGACCUCGAGGGCCAUGCAGGACCCUGUGUUCCAGCUUCCAACUGCAGGAAGAACACCAAAUGGUGAGGUUGGGGCCAUGGAUCUCACACAGCUACAGAAGGAGAAACAGGACUUGGAGCAGCAACUUCUGGAGAAAAAUAAGACCAUAAAGCAGAUGCAGCAGCGGAUGCUGGAGCUCCGGAAGACUCUGCAGAAGGAGCUGAAAAUCAGACCCGAUAAUGAGCUCUUCGAAGUCCGGGAGAAACCUGGACCUGAGAUGGCAAACAUGGCGCCUUCCGUCACGAAUAACACUGACCUGACAGAUGCCCGCGAGAUCAACUUUGAGUACCUUAAACAUGUGGUUUUAAAAUUCAUGUCUUGUCGCGAAUCCGAGGCUUUUCAUCUUAUAAAAGCUGUGUCAGUGUUGCUGAACUUUUCCCAAGAGGAGGAGAACAUGCUCAAGGAAACUCUGGAAUAUAAGAUGUCAUGGUUUGGGUCCAAACCAGCUCCCAAGGGCAGCAUCCGGCCGUCUAUCUCAAACCCUCGGAUACCAUGGUCCUAGAGGGGACUACCCAAGGAUGGAGCUCCGUGGGUUGACACUUUUUCUGUGAAAAGAACACUGACACACCAGUCUGGGUGGGUUUUUAAUCACUGUAACUGCAGUAUUUUGUACAAGUGUCUAAACAUUGUUUACAAGACUAAGGCCCACUUCCCUGCAGGCUGACCUGAACCUCAGGGGGUAGCUGAUCCUGUCAUUCUGGUCACCAAACAGGAGGGUCCUGGCACUACCCAGAUUUCCACAGUGCUGCUAAUAUCCCAGCUCCAGCCAGCACCCCAUCUGCACCUGAAUCCUCUAACUUCACGGUAGCACUUACAGCUGAAGCCAUCAGCAUCUGGCAGGCACACCUGAGUCACCAUGUAGCGCUGCUACUGGAGGUAGAGACGGCCCUUUGAGAUGGUGCCCAGCAGGCCAAACCCACCUGCCUCUGCCAGGAACAGCCAACUCCAUGGGAACUCUAUGGGAGUGGCUUUUAAAAAUUCAGAUGAGUUAGAAGCUUUUUAUCCCUUCCUCUCAAGAAAAUAUUCUUUCACCCUGUCUCUCAAACCACCUAGAACUUUAGAGGAUCCAUCUUUAAGGGUCGGUGUGGAUGAAUGAGAAAAUGCACCUUUCUGACAGUAUCUCCACUUUACUUAAGAAAACUAGCAAAUAUAUGAAAAGACCCUUAGUACCAAAUACACUCAAUUGCCUUUUUAAUGAAUGUACUUGUCUUGGAUAGGUUGCUGGUAAACCAUUUUAAACUAUUUUUUAUAGCUGAAGUUCUUCACUACUAUAAACAUGUCUUCUGUACUAUAAAAUCCAUUUAACUGGUGUUCUUAAAAUCAGAGCGUCCAGAGGAAAUUCUUCCUAAAACUAGGAUUCCUGUUCCUUUGUCUUCUCACUCGCACUCUGGCACUGCUCCCUCUGAAGUGCAGUGGGAUCUCGUGUGCUUUGUCUUGAUUCUGUGCUGCGCUGCCGCUGGGCGAUGCAGACCACCUGUCUUCUACUGAAGGACAGUCCGCUGUCUCCAGUGGGGGCAGCAGCUGUCCCCCAGCCUCGAUGGAGACACUGGGGCAGUCUGCCUUGUCUGUGGAGCUGCUCUCUCUCCCUCAUCCCACCCCAAAUACUUAAAAUGACACUACACCCAGACGGCGCCCAGCUGGCUGCAGCACUUGUAGCAUGCACAUGACUCUGGUAGUAACCAACAAAAACUUGUUUUAUGGAUUCCUCGUUUACUGAGGAAAGGGAACAUGCUGGUUCUGGAAAAGCCACAAUAUUGAAUCUAAAAGGAAACCGUUUAUUGUUUGAUGAAAGUUUCACUGGUUAAAUAAAAAACUAAAUUAAUAACUGGAGCCUCUAAAUUUAUUAUCCAUUAUCCAGUGAUGGAAAGUUGUAUUUCUCAAUCAUGCUUAGGGCCAAAAUAGGUAUAUAAAAUGUGUCACAGAAAAACACGCAUUUGCAACGUUAACCUAACGAAAUUUCCAUGAAGAACCAAGUCAGGGCAGCAUCUCCUUAGUCCCAGCUCAGGCUCUCUGCCUUCCAGAGGCCGCUUCUCCAGUGACUAACCUCCUCCUCUGGCUCCUCCUUGCAGACAGUUAUCCCUUGUUUAGAACACGAAUUUCCAUUUACCUGGUGGGAACACGAAACAGGAGUCUCUUCUGUUCUGCAAGUUUGAUGGGUAAGAGGUAGCCUUUUUUCAAAGUAGGAUUUCCUUUUUCAACUGUUCCAGGAAAGAAUCUCUAAGACUGGGUAGCUCACAGCCAGCCAAAGGCAGCUACAUUUCCACAGAAGCCCAUCCGCUGCCUCCGUGGCUUCUCCAGCCAUUGAACUGGUCCCACACGCACCCCAGGCCCCACUCCUCGGCAGUUUCAGGUGUAGCUGUGGGGCCCGUUCCUAGGUCUGUACUCACUUUAGGGAGGCUUCACUGACUAGGCUUUCCUCCUGCAUGUUGAAUUUCCUUCAGCUUUAAGAGGAAGAGUGGAAUAAAUAUUCUAAGUGAUUUAAUGCACUUUGACUUGUAUAAAACUUUCUGUGUUAGCGACGGUAUCUAUAGCCCUUUAUACGAGCGAUGGAUCUUGAGCUCUCCUUCCAUGUUGUAAAUAGGGAUUGUAUUCUUGAAAACUGCUGUAGCAAAUUCAUCUGUGGUGCAAUACACUUUUUGAUUAAAGCUCUUCAAUCCAGAUGCAACUACAAUGGAUUUUACUAGUUUGGUGUGUCAGUAUUUCUUUGACUCAUUAAAUCUGGUAUUUUGUGUCUCAUAUUUAACACUCCAAGGCCAA